GAUAAUGCAUAGUAUAUGUACAUAUACUUACCUGCACACAGACACCUUUUGGUUAUACACAUAUGCAUAAAAACAUAAGUUUUUAAUUAAAAGAUGUAGGUCCUGUAUUUUAUGAAUUCAUGAAUGCCUGAGAAUGUCUUUCUGUUGCUUUGUUAUAUAGGAGCUACUUAAUUGGGAAUAAUAUUUAUGGUUUGUCUAUAAACUAAUUUCAAUGGGCAUUUGGGGUGGCUGGAAGCUAUGGAGCUAUGUGGUUUUGCUCCUUGUUGAGCUAUAAGCAUUCAAACAAGUCCCCCUUUUUUUUCUUCACUAUUUUUUUUCAACUCUUGUGCCAAUAGAUGUGUGGAUUGUUUUCCGUUAACUCUACCUGGAAAGUGAUGAGUCCUUUUGAUGUACAUAAUCACGUCCUUAUUUUUUCCCCUGUGCUGAAAUAUUUCUUUAUCCCUUUGUUUGUUGUUUGCAUUUCAAAUCUUAUCAAGUACUCAAAUUCUAUCAUUGUUUGACAAACUGAUAUUUUCUGGCCUUUUUAUCAAUCACAUCUGCAUUCAUUUUCAUCCUUAUCCUUUAUUUCUUAAUUUAGUUACAGAUUAAGUUUAUCCUCCUCAGGACUGUAUGUAAGUUUUCGUUGUCAAUUCUACUGUUUAUUGUAUCUAAGGUGGGUUUCGUAAUUCUAACAGAAACCAGUAGAAUAGGAUGUUCAUCAAGUUAGUAACAAUAGUUUAAUAGUAUCUUUGUGCUGAAUGAGGUAGGAAGUUGCAUGCUGAACAAAGCAAGGCUUGGGAAAUUGAUAUUUUUCAUAGAUAUGUGUUAGGAAUAGUGAACACUGACAUCAAGGGAUAUGUGGAUAUGGGUGUUUAUUUUUUCUCCCUAGAUGACAGGAUGCUUGCUCUUCACUAACUGAAUGAUACGUACACUAAUUGACUUAUACUGUAGAAAUAGGAGAAGAGGAGUAUGAAUACAUGGACUCCAAUAAAUACAUUGAGCAUCUGCUGACUCAGCUUGAGGAGCAACACAGGAGUCUCUGGAGGGAGAAGUUGGCAGUGGCCCGACUACAGCGAGAAGUUGCCCAAAGAACAAGUGAGGGGGCCAUGCAUGAGAAGCUGAUACAUGAACUGGAAGAGGAGAGACACUUACGUCUUCAAAGCGAGAAGCGGUUGCAGGAGGUGACCCUAGAGUCUGAACGCAACAGAAUUCAGAUGCGUAGCUUGCAGCAGCAGUUCUCCAGGAUGGAAGAAACAGUACGAAAUCUAUUGCAGAGUCAAGGAUCUCCAGAGCAGAAAAAAGAAGAAACUGUUAAUAUAAUGGUCUAUCAGGAAAAGCUGUCAGAGGAAGAGAGAAAACAUAAGGAAGCUUUGGAAGAUCUUCACAUGGUGGUUGAUGAGGAUUCGAGGAGUGAAAGCAGCAGUACAGAUGAGGGAAAAGAAAAGACCAAAUUGCUAUUAGAGAGAUUGAAAGCUCUAGAGGCAGAGAAUUCAGCGUUGGCUUUGGAGAAUGAAAAUCAAAGGGAACAAUAUGAGCGAUGUCUUGAUGAGGUAGCCAACCAAGUUGUUCAAGCUCUGCUUACUCAAAAGGAUCUAAGAGAGGAAUGUGUGAAGUUGAAAACAAGAGUGUUUGAUUUGGAACAGCAGAAUCGAACACUAAGCAUCCUAUUCCAACAGCGAGUCAGACCCACUUCUGAUCUGCUCCUCCAGAAACUUCACUCACGUCUCUUGGAUCUUUCAUCUGGAGAUUUGCUUUCAGAGGUGGAAAGAAACCGAAGUCUGACACAGUCACGAACUGAUGCUGAGGUGCACGAACACCAACUAAAUACAAAAUCGGCCUUGAAAUGCCCUGGCUUGGGGGCUGUCAUCCCUGGUCAUCUCUGUCCUCGAAACAGCUACAGUAGCAGCAGUGAACUGUCUCUUUCAAGCACCUGCAGCGAGUACUCCAGUGGCUCCUCCUACACGUGGCACGAUGGGAAGAACCUCAGGAAAAGGCAAUCAUCACAAAACUGGGAUAAAAGGCUAAGUAUUGAUUCUUCGCUCCCAAGUGGCUUUGCUAGUCCUACAAAUGAACUACCUCCAACUCGUAUCAAGGAAAGCCACAUUUUGGAAGGGCUAAGAAAGCUACAGAAGCGAAAAGUGUUACUUGAACCCCCAUCAGUGAUAACCAAAUGGGGUUAUAAAGAUUGCAUGAACUCGAAUGAAGGAAUAUAUUCUCCUGGAAUUAAAAGUAGCAGCCUCAAGGAGUAUCCCCCCUGCAAAACAGCUGACCUGGGGAGCCCCUGCAAGGAACCCCACAAGACAUUUGUUUAUGAUCUAGAUUCCCACGUUGAUGCGGACGAUGACCCUUCCACCUUAGCAUUGCUCCAAGCAGUUCCAAACCAGAGCUGCAGGCCACAUGGCAGUAAAUUAACCCACAGUGUUUCCGACAGUCUGUUUGGCUGGGAGACAAACAGAAAACACUUUCUGGAAGGCACAUCCUCAGUUUAUCCCAAGGAAAGGCCUGAAAAGCUGACAAGUUGCGCCAGCAGCUGUCCCUUAGAGAUGAAGCUGUGCCCAAGUGUGCAGACGCCUCAGGUACAGAGGGAGAGGGGCCCACAGGGCCAAGGCCAUGGCCGCAUGGCUCUCAACCUCCAGCUUUCAGACACUGAUGACAAUGAAACGUUUGAUGAGCUGCACAUAGAGAGCAGUGAUGAGAAAAGUCCUUCAGACGUGUCAUUGGCUGCCGACACCGAUAAGUCCGUGGAGAACCUGGAUGUCCUUGUGGGGUUUGGAAAAUCUCUAUGUGGGUCUCCUGAAGAGGAGGAAAAACAAGUGCCCAUCCCUUCAGAGACUAGGCCAAAGACUUUUAGUUUCAUUAAGCAGCAAAGAGUUGUAAAAAGGACUUCUUCAGAAGAAUGUGUGACUGUGAUAUUUGAUGCGGAAGACGGUGAGCCCAUUGAAUUCAGCUCUCACCAGACUGGGGUUGUCACUGUUACCAGAAAUGAGAUUUCCAUCAAUUCAACUCCUGCUGGACCCAAGGCAGAACAUACUGAGCUUUUACCUCAGGGAAUUGCUUGUUUACAGCCAAGAGCUGCUGCAAGAGACUAUACUUUCUUUAAAAGGUCUGAAGAGGACACUGAGAAAAACAUUCCAAAAGAUAAUGUAGAUAAUGUUCCCAGGGUGUCCACUGAAUCUUUCAGCUCCAGGACAGUGACACAAAAUCCUCAGCAGCAAAAGCUGGUCAAACCAACACACAAUAUAUCAUGCCAGAGUAAUUCCAGGUCUUCGGCACCCAUGGGCAUCUAUCAAAAGCAAAAUCUGACAAAAAUACCUCCCAGGGGCAAGUCUUCACCUCAGAAAUCAAAACUAAUGGAGCCCGAAGCCACCACACUACUCCCUUCAUCUGGCCUGGUGACUCUUGAAAAAUCACCAGCCUUAGCUCCUGGGAAACUCUCACGAUUCAUGAAGACUGAGAGCUCAGGGCCCCUCUUUGAAUUACGAUCAGAUCCACACAUUCCAAAACAUUCCGCCCAACUUCCGCACAGCUCCAGGAUGCCCAGCAGGAGGGACUGGGUCCAGUGCCCCAAGAGUCAGACUCCAGGGUCACGGUCAAGGCCUGCCAUUGAGUCUAGUGACAGUGGAGAGCCCCCCACGAGGGAUGAACACUGUGGCUCUGGGCCGGAGGCAGGGGUGAAAUCCCCUUCCCCUCCGCCCCCUCCAGGCAGGUCCGUCUCCCUGCUGGCCAGGCCCAGCUAUGACUAUUCACCAGCACCUUCAUCCACCAAGUCCGAAACCAGGGUCCCCAGUGAAACAGCAAGGACCCCAUUCAAAUCCCCGCUGCUGAAAGGAAUUUCUGCUCCAGUUAUUUCUUCUAAUCCGGCCACGACAGAAGUGCAGAGGAAGAAACCUUCUGUGGCCUUCAAAAAGCCUAUCUUCACUCACCCUAUGCCCUCCCCAGAAGCAGUCAUUCAAACCCGAUGCCCUGCUCAUGCCCCCUCCAGCUCCUUCACCGUAAUGGCUCUGGGGCCUCCAAAGGUCUCUCCGAAGAGAGGUGUCCCCAAAACCUCUCCUCGCCAAACACUUGGGACCCCACAAAGGGACAUAGGAUUACAGACUCCCAGGAUCUCUCCUUCAACCCAUGAGCCACUGGAAAUGACGUCCUCCAAAAGUGUAUCUCCAGGGAGAAAAGGACAAUUGAAUGAUAGCGCCUCCACACCCCCCAAGCCUUCCUUCUUAGGGGUAAAUGAGUCACCAUCAUCUCAGGUCAGCAGUUCCUCAUCAUCCUCAUCACCCGCCAAAAGCCAUAACAGCCCUCAUGGUUGUCAAAGUGCUCAUGAGAAAGGACUGAAAACUCGCCUUCCAGUGGGACUCAAAGUGCUCAUGAAGUCUCCCCAGCUGCUCAGGAAAAGUUCCACCGUGCCAGGGAAACAUGAAAAAGACAGUUUAAAUGAAGCCUCCAAAAGUUCCGUGGCUGUGAACAAGUCUAAGCCAGAGGACUCCAAGAAUCCAGCAAGCAUGGAGAUCACAGCGGGUGAAAGAAAUGUGACCCUACCGGAUUCACAAGCACAGGGCAGUUUAGCUGAUGGGCUUCCCCUGGAAACAGCACUACAAGAGCCAUUGGAAAGUAGCAUCCCUGGGAGUGAUGGAAGGGAUGGGGUAGAUAAUAGAUCCAUGAGAAGAUCCCUUUCCUCCAGCAAACCACACCUAAAACCAGCUCUGGGUAUGAAUGGCGCCAAAGCCCGCAGCCACAGCUUCAGUACACACUCAGGAGACAAGCCUUCUACGCCCCCCAUCGAAGGGUCAGGCAAAGUCCGCACUCAGAUCAUUACCAAUACCGCCGAGAGAGGCAAUUCUCUUACCCGGCAGAACUCUUCCACGGAAAGCUCUCCCAACAAGGCCCCUUCUGCUCCCAUGUUGGAGAGUCUCCCCAGUGUUGGGAGGCCCUCGGGGCACCCCUCCUCCGGGAAGGGCUCCCUGGGGAGCUCAGGCAGCUUCAGCAGUCAGCAUGGGAGCCCAAGUAAGUUGCCUUUGAGGAUCCCUCCAAAGUCUGAGGGACUCCUCAUCCCACCUGGAAAGGAAGACCAGCAGGCCUUCACCCAGGGAGAGUGCCCCAGUGCCAAUGUGGCUGUACUUGGGGAACCAGGCAGUGACCGCCGCAGUUGCCCACCCACCCCAACAGACUGCCCUGAAGCCCUGCAGAGCCCAGGGAGGACUCAGCAUCCAAGCACUUUUGAAACAAGCAGUACAUCCAAGCUAGAAACUUCUGGAAGGCAUCCAGAUGCCUCUGCAACCGCGACUGAUGCUGUGAGUUCAGAAGCCCCCCUCUCACCCACAAUCGAAGAAAAGGUCAUGUUGUGCAUUCAGGAAAAUGUGGAAAAGGGCCAAGUGCAAACAAAGCCCACCUCUGUGGAAGCAAAGCAGAAGCCUGGGCCUUCUUUUGCCAGCUGGUUUGGUUUUCGGAAGAGUAGACUUCCAGCUCUGAGUAGCAGGAAAAUGGACAUCUCCAAAACCAAAGUAGAAAAGAAAGAUGCAAAAGUCUUGGGGUUUGGAAACAGACAACUAAAAUCAGAAAGAAAAAAAGAGAAAAAGAAGCCUGAACUACAGUGUGAGACAGAAAAUGAGCUUAUCAAGGACACCAAGUCAGCAGAUAAUCCAGAUGGCGGUUUACAAAGCAAAAAUAAUCGGAGAACACCACAAGACAUUUACAACCAACUGAAGAUUGAACCAAGGAAUAGACACAGCCCUGUUGCAUGUUCAACGAAAGACACCUUCAUGACGGAACUCUUGAACAGAGUUGAUAAGAAAGCAGCUCCACAGACAGAAAGUGGAUCAAGUAAUGCUUCCUGCAGGAAUGUGUUAAAGGGCAGUUCUCAGGGCUCCUGUCUCAUCGGCAGCUCUAUCAGUACUCAAGGAAACCACAAGAAAAACAUGAAAAUCAAAGCCGAUAUGGAAGUACCAAAAGACUCCCUGGUAAAAGAGGCAAAUGAAAACUUGCAAGAGGAUGAAGACGAUGCAGUUGCAGAUUCUGUAUUUCAGAGCCACAUCAUAGAAUCCAACUGCCAGAUGAGAACAUUGGACAGUGGGAUCGGAACCUUUCCACUCCCAGACUCGGGAAAUCGCUCGACAGGACGCUACCUAUGCCAGCCAGACUCCCCAGAGGACGCUGAGCCUCUCCUGCCUCUCCAGUCAGCCCUUUCUGCAGUUUCUUCCAUGAGAGCCCAAACCCUUGAACGUGAAGUGCCUUCCUCCACAGACGGCCAGCGCCCUGCAGAUAGCGCCAUUGUUCAUUCCACAUCCGACCCCAUCAUGACCGCCAGAGGGAUGAGGCCUCUUCAGAGCCGCCUCCCCAAACCAGCUUCCUCAGGAAAAGUCAGUUCCCAAAAGCAGAAUGAAGCAGAGCCAAGGCCUCAGACAUGCUCAUCAUUCGGAUAUGCUGAAGACCCAAUGGCAAGCCAGCCGCUUCCAGACUGGGGGAGUGAAGUUGCUGCCACCGGGACCCAGAAAUUGAGACAACUUGAAGAAACAAAAGACGAUCCCGAGAAUAGAUUAUCGAAAAUUUCCCUAGAGUCAUUCAAUAAAUUUAACAGCAAUACUGUGAUUUUAUUAGAAAAAGAGAAGAACUCUCUGAACAAGGUUGAAGGACAGAAGGAAGAAAAAGAAAAAAAUGAAGAGACAUCUUUGAGUAGUUCAGAUAGGCCUGGGGUAGACAACUUGGAAUCUUUGAGUGAUUCUUUAUAUGAUAGCUUCUCUUCCUGUGCCAGUCAAGGUUCAAAUGAUGUAUAAAGGACAUCUCUUCCCUUAGUGAGCUGGGACUGGAGCGCUUAAGAAAUGAUGGGUGGGGGGUGGGGGGUGCACCGCUUGAUAGAGAUAACAAUAAACUAUUGCAGUACCAGAGCCUUCCUUGUCAAAUUCACAGCAGGCAACCCACCAGAGCUUAUUUCUCUGACAGGGCAAUAAAGAUAGACUCCAUUUAUUGUGUUUCAAGAGGAUUAAGCGUAAACACAUCUAUGAUACAGAAUCCUUAAUUUUGCACUUUUUUUGAAUAUUUGUACAGAAGUUGUAAAUUUUUUGGAAGAGAAAUUAUAUUUGUAGCAAAAAAAGACAGCAAUAAAUGGAAUCAGUGCCAUGCUCUUGAAAUAAUGUACUAAGUCUUAGAAGUUGAUGAUAAUAUAUAUUUUUUAAAAUCCCAACUGAAGUUUUUGUGAAGUUCGUUGUCCUGGUCCUCAAAUUGUUUGUGGGUACACUCUGUAAACCUACAACAGGGCCUGCCAAAAAAUCGGAGGGUUCCUCCUCAUCUCCAUCUCACAAAUCUCAAUUUGAUGGAAAUGUUCAUUUUAGUGUAAUUUCAGAUUCGUUGCCAGAGAUUCAGGUGAUAGUAAUAAGUGUCAUUCUGCUUCUGCUGAAAAAUGAAAAGGGUCCUGAAGUGUGGACACUGAUUGGGAGUGUGACAUUGUAUCAGAAAUGACCGAAUUCUAUUCCCAAUACCAGUUUUUCCUUCCAGACAUUUCUUUAGAUUGUCUUUUACUUAGUGCUUCUCUAUGAUCCUGAAUAUUAUUUGAUUUUUAUCUUCUUGCUCUUUUUAUUAAAAUCUGGGCACUCUAAAAAUGAAAACAAAUUUCUAUUUGCAAUGUUCACUUUUAAAAAUAAAAUUAAUGGUGCUACGAAGAAUUCUUUUUAAUAUCCUUUUUUUUCUACAAAGACUGUUUAUAUGUAAGGAUAAAUUCUAUUUUAAAGGUUAUGUGUAUUUUUUCUAGAUGUGAACUAUUUAUAAUUACUUAUGUACAGGAGCUUGUAAACUAGGCCCAAUAGAAAUAUUUUUAGGAUCUAUAUGGCUACUUUAGCACAUAAUUGUUUCUUUAAAGAGUAUUGUAUGAUCAGUGUUAUUUGGUUAAUUUGUGCAAUUUGUUUUAUUUUAUCUUAAAUGAAAAUUAUGUAAAAUGUCCUUGUCUUUCAGACUUUAAAAAAUCUUUUUGUUUCCUUUCUGAAUAAAAGUUAUAUCACAUUUGCACCCUCUGAAAA